AGUCACACAGCGACGUAGAGGUGACUGGAGGUAUAUACUUGUCCUCACCUGGAUCAUGCUGAUGUGGCCCCAACCCCACCUCCCUACCCAUCCCCACCUCCCUACCCAUCCCCACCUCCCUACCCAUCCUAUGAUGUCCAAAGAAACCAGACAGAGCAAAUUGGCCGAGGCCAAGGAACAGUUGACAGACCAUCAUCCCCAGACCAACCCUAGUGUUGGUACAGCAGCAAGCGACACCAAAAAGAAGAAAAUAAAUAAUGGCACUAACCCUGAGACAACCACUUCUGGUGGUUGCCACUCGCCUGAGGAUGAACAGAAGGCAAGCCACCAACAUCAGGAAGCCCUAAGGAGGGAGCUAGAGGCCCAGGUUCAUACCAUACGAAUCCUUACAUGUCAGAAAACUGAGCUUCAGAUGGCACUCUACUACAGCCAGCAUGCUGUCAAGCAGUUGGAAGGAGAGGCCAGGGAUCUGAUCAGCCGCCUGCAUGAUUCAUGGAAGUUUGCAGGAGAGUUAGAGCAGGCUCUCUCUGCUGUCGCUACACAGAAGAAGAAGGCGGAUAGGUACAUUGAGGAGUUAACAAAGGAGAGGGACGCCCUGAGUCUGGAACUGUACAGGAACACCAUAACUGAUGAGGAGCUGAAGGAGAAAAAUGCCAAACUACAAGAAAAACUUCAACUUGUAGAAUCUGAAAAGUCUGAGAUCCAGCUCAACGUAAAGGAGCUAAAAAGGAAACUGGAGAGGGCCAAGCUCCUGCUGCCACAGCAGCAGCUGCAGGCGGAGGCUGACCACCUGGGUAAGGAGCUGCAGAGUGUGUCAGCAAAGCUCCAAGCCCAGGUGGAAGAGAACGAGUUGUGGAACCGCCUGAACCAGCAACAGGAGGAGAAGAUGUGGAGGCAGGAGGAGAAGAUACAGGAGUGGGAGGAGAAGAUACAGGAGCAGGAGGAGAAGAUACGGGAGCAGGAGGAGAAGAUACGGGAGCAGGAGGAGAAGAUGCGGAGGCAGGAGGAGAUGAUGUGGGAGAAGGAGGAGAAGAUGCGGAGGCAGGAGGAGAUGAUGUGGGAGAAGGAGGAGAAGAUGCGGAGGCUGGAGGAGAUGAUGUGGGAGAAGGAGGAGAAGAUACGGGAGCUGGAAGAGAAGAUGCACGAGCAGGAGAAGAUACGGGAGCAGGAAGAGAAGAGGCAGGAGGAGGAGAAGAUACGCGAGCAGGAGAAGAGGCAGGAGCAGGAGGCGAAGAUGUGGAGGCAGGAGGAGAAGAUACGGGAGCAGGAAGAGAAGAUACGGGAGCAGGAGAAAAAGAUGUGGAGGCAGGAGGAGAAGAUUCACGAGCAGGAGAAGAUACGGGAGGAGGAGAAGAGGCAGGAGCAGGAGGAGAUGUGGAGGCAGGAGGAGAAGAUAAGGGAGCAGGAGGAGAUAUGGAGGCAAAAGGAGAAGAUGCACGAGCAGGAGAAGAUACGGAAGCAGGAGGAGAAGGUGUGGAGGCAGGAGGAGAAGAUGCACGACCAGGAGGAGAAGAUACGGGAGCAGGAGGAGAAGAUGUGGAGGCAGGAGGAGAAGAUAAGGGAGCAGGAGGAGAAGAUACGGGAGCAGGAGGAGAAGAUACGGGAGCAGGAGGAGAAGAUACGAGAGCAGGAGGAGAUGAUGCAGGAACAGGAAGAGAAGAUGGGGGAGCAGGAAGAGAAGAUGCAAGAACAGGAGAAGAUGCGGAGGCAGGAGGAGAAGAUAAGGGAGCAGGAGGAGAAGAUACGGGAGCAGAAGGAGAAGAUACGAGAGCAGGAGGAGAAGAUAUGGGAGCAGGAGGAGAAGAUACGAGAGCAGGAGGAGAUGAUGCAGGAACAGGAAGAGAAGAUGUGGGAGCAGGAGGAGAAGAUGUGUGAGCAGGAAGAGAAGAUGCAAGAACAGGAGGAGAAGAUGCGGAGGCAGGAGGAGAAGAUGUGGGAGCAGGAAGUGAGGCUGCGGCAGCAGGAGGAGAAGAUGCAGGAACACCAGGUGGAGCUGAAGAGCCAAGAGGCUGAGUCUGCAGCAGCAGCGAGACCAUUACCUGGGUCACCUGCAGCAGAGCACCUGGAAGCUGCCAUCUAAUGAGCACAUGACAAGAAGGCAAAGACAAUAAACAUGUAAAAGCCGGCAGCAAGGCCUGGAGAAGAGUAAGCCGCCAUGUGACUGUUUAGAAUAUAGUCUGAGCACAAACCUGAAAAAAAAAUUUUAUUUAUUUUAAAUUGUGGCAAAAUACUGGCCAGGCAUGGUAGCUCACGCCUGUAAUCCUAGCAAUUUGGGAGGCCGAGGUAAAUGGAUGACCUGAGGUCAAGAGUUCAAGACCAGCCUGGCCAAUACAAAAAUUAGCCGGGCAUGGUGGCGCAUGCCUGUAAUCCCAGCUACUUGGGAGGCUGAGGCAGGAGAAUCGCUUGAACCUGGGAGGCAGAGGUUGCAGUGAGCUGAGAUCGUGCCACUGCACUCAAGCCUGGGUGACAGAGCGAAACUCCGUCUCAAAAAAAAAAGUUUCUUCCUUACAUGUAUGUUUCUAUUAGUUUUCUUCUUGGUCUUUCUCAUUUAGUCUUGUGUUGUCUUUUGACAUUCAUAGUAAACUUUUAUCUGCCUCCAGAGAGUAUUGACUUUGAGUUUAUGGCACACAAUUGGAGUAAGGGCAGAUCGCCUUCAUCUACUUUGGGACUAAGCUGGUUCAAAGCAGGUUUUAGGUUUUCUGAUGGCUGGUCUAUGUUUUAUUCAUUUGGACUCCCAGGGGUGGCCCUUCCAGGGUCCCCACCAAGGUCCCAUCUCCUUCCUGGGACCCAAAUUCUCAUUAGGUCAUUUCAGCCCUGUGAGAGUGCCAAACAUUCAGCUAGGCUCUCCAGCCUCUUAACUACCACUUCAUACUCAGUUUCUUAGCCUCUUAGCCCUCUACUGUUGACCAAUCACCAAAUGUGGGAAAGCACUACAGACUGUCAGGAUCACCUCCUAGGCCUGGUCACUCAAGUCCUGACUGAGGUCUCCAAUUACCUUCCAACAAUUGUUUUUGAUUGGGGGCGGGGCACAUUUUUAUCCAGUUUUUCUAACUGCUCUUGUGGGGAGGCGAAUCUGUAACAAGCUCCUCUGCCUUUACUGAAAGUUGAAAACCUUCAUCUGUCCUUUUUUUGUUGUUGUUGAGAUGGAGUCUUGCGCUGUUGCCCAGGCUCUAGUGCAAUGGCACGAUCUCUGCUCACUGUAACCUCUGCCUCCUGGGUUCAAGCAAUUCUCCUGCCUCAGCUUCCCGAGUAGCGUGUGCCACCAUGCCUGGCUAAUUUUUUUUUAUACCUUUAAUAGAGGCAGGAUGUCACCAUGUUUUCCAGGCUGGUCUCGAGCUCCUGACUCAGGUGAUCUACCUGCCUCAGCCUCCCAAAGUGCUGGGAUUACAAGUAUGAGCCACUGCAUCCGGCCCAUCUGUCUUUUAAAACAUGUUUUUAAUUGGAGGUAUAAUUUCUAUUAGUGAAAUGCACAGGUCUGGUUUACAUUUUGAUGAGUUUUAACUCAUUUAACAUUACUAUGGAACCCACCUCCUUUGAAGAUACAGAGUAUUUCUAUCAUCCAGAAAGUUCUCCUGUGCUUUCAUGCUGUCCCGCACUCCCCCAGCAGCUGAUGAACAUGCUGAGGACAUUGGUACUGGAUUCUGGCCGCCCCAAAAGAGCCGCUUUGACCAGGCUUACCCAGCACUAAAUCCCUGCCUGCUCUCUCAAAAUUUCCAUCUUUAAACUGGUUGUACCUAUAACCCUCCCUCAUCAAGUCAAUAGAUAAACAAACCCUGAAAAAUAAACAACUCUUCCUGGCC